AGUAGCGGCUGUGUAUCGGUGACGCGGGUGUUUCCCCAGUUUGUGGCCCCUGAGUGCUGGGGGGGGACCGCGGUGACUGAACCUAGAAGGUGGAGAGGAAUCGUCCUCGGUGCCCAGAGGCGGCUCUGCAGCCCCGUGACGGCGACCACUGCUCCCGGGCCGUGCUUCCCCAAGUAGUCCGAUGGCAGCGGCUGCGCCGAGGCGCCCGACUCAGGUAAUUGUGGCGCCUUCUGUGCCCUCAGGUCACCCCAUCGUCACCCAGGUCCUAAACCAGCGAGGGAGCGGCUCCUGCUCACGGGUCUGUAGCCGGUACCCGGCGUAGGAACACUGAGGCGCUCGCAGGAGGGGUCCCUGUGUAACUGUCCAGUGGGGGUCCCUGUGUAACUGUCCAGUGGGUUCACCUUGCCAGCUGCCUAGACAGAGCCGAUUUAUGAAGACUGGAGAAUUGCGAUGGAGAAAUAGUAAUUGACGCAGAGCCGUCAGGCUGUUCUGGAGACAGGAGUUUUAUUAUUACUCAAAUCAGUCUCCAUUAGCAUUCCGGGAUCAGAGUUUUCAACAUUAAUUUGGCGGUAAGGGUUGGGACCUGAGAUGGAUUCAUAGAGGGUUAAAGUGAGUUUUUCAUGCUGUUUUCUGUUCUGGGUGGGAUGGCAGAACUGAUUGACCCAGAUUACCGGUCUGUGUGUUGUCAGCUGAUCCAUCCAGUGCAGGAUCUGCAAAAUACCUCAAGCACUGAUCUUAGGUUUUACAAUAGUGAUUUAUCUUCAGGAGCAACUUGGGGAGGUUCAGACUCUUGGAGUCAGAAGCUGCAUGACCCCUAAACGGUAAUUUCUAACCUUGUAGCUAAUUCGUUAGUCCUGCAAAGGCAGGCUGUUCUCCAGGCAAGAAGGGGGUCUUUUCAGGAAAGGGCUAUUAUCAAUUUUGUUUCAGAGUGAAACCAUGAACUGAAUUCCUUCCCUAAGUUAAUUCAGCCUAUACCCAGGAAUGAACAAGGACAGCUGAAAGGUUGGAAGCAAGACGGAGUCAGUAAGGUCUGAUUUCUUUCACUGUCAUAAUUUCCUCAGUUAUAAUUUUGCAAAGACGGUUUCACCUGUUUCUGACACCCGUGGGAUGCGGUGGGGAGAGCAACAAGCACAGGGAGGGGCGCAGGCAAUGGCCUGGAGAUGGACGGAGCCGGGAGGAUGGAACCUGUCUGGAACAAAGUGUGAGGUGGAGCUCUCCCUGGAAGAGUAAGCAGGCCGAGGGCUGUGCAUUCAAGGUGAGGACGCUAGAAGCCAUGGAGAGUUUUGAAUAAAGGAGGGACAUGAUCCAAAUCCAGGCUUUUAAGGUUUCCCAAAGGACAUUCAAAGGAAGAAUAUCGUAGAGAGGAUGAAGACUUUGGGGUCUUGGGAGGUUGAAUCCUUUUUGUAGCUCACAUAGGUGGUAGAGAUGACAUUUUGCACUGAGACAAGCAGGUCAGACAACCAGCCGUAGGGUUACCUGGUUCCAGGGACAAGAAAGGGUUCAGGGAGGCCUGAGCUUAUCAAAUCCCGUGACAUGUUUGUAAUGUCUGCCUCUCCCCUCAGGCACUCCUGGCUGCAGAAGCACUUAGGGAACCCACACAGGGAAGUGGAGGGUGUUCAAUCCCCUCAUUGGUCUUGACCCCAUCCACAGGUUCUCUAGCUUGUGGUGUGCUGGGACUCUUAAGUGCCAUUUUUUCAGUCCUUUGAUCCGAGGACCCUGGAGAAUCUCUAAAGACAGGAUACUGAGGCCAUGGCAGGUUAUAUGCAAGUAUGCCCAUUUCUGUCAGCCAGUGUAAACACUCUUGUAAGAUUAACCCAGGAUUUGCUACCAGGUUGUGAAAUGCUUAGAGAUAAAAAGGAUCAAAGUCAGAAGGUGAUAUUACCACAGUUCUACUGGCUACCGGCUUCAUCUGGUUGGACCUUGGUGCACACACUAUGGGUUGAGGGAAGAGGAAGAAAUGUCAGAGAUAAGGCUCCUGCCAUAAUCCAGCAGGGCACUGUGACCUUUGAAGAUGUGGCUGUGAACUUUUCCCAGGAGGAGUGGUGUCUUCUUAGUGAGGCUCAGAGGUGCUUGUACCGUGAUGUGAUGCUAGAGAACCUGGCUCUCAUAUCCUCGCUGGGUUGUUGGUGUGGAUCAAAAGAUGAGGAGGCACCUUGUAAGCAGAGAAUUUCUGUACAAAGAGAGUCUCAGAGCAGGACUCCUAGGGCAGGUGUUUCUCCUAAGAAGGCUCACCCCUGUGAAAUGUGUGGCCUCAUCUUGGAGGAUGUUUUUCACUUUGCUGACCACCAGGAAACUCAUCACAAGCAGAAGCUGAACAGGAGUGGAGCAUGUGGAAAAAACUUGGAUGACACUGCAUACCUUCAUCAGCACCAGAAGCAGCAUAUUGGAGAGAAAUUCUACAGAAAGAGUGUCAGAGAAGCAUCGUUUGUAAAGAAACGUAAGCUCAGGGUGUCACAGGAGCCAUUUGUCUUCCGCGAGUUUGGGAAGGACGUUCUGCCCAGUUCAGGAUUGUGCCAAGAAGCAGCUGCUGUAGAGAAGACAGACAGUGAAACUAUGCAUGGCCCACCCUUUCAGGAGGGAAAAACUAAUUACAGUUGUGGAAAACGCACAAAAGCCUUCAGCACCAAACACUCAGUUAUUCCACACCAGAAACUUUUCACUAGAGAUGGAUGUUAUGUGUGCAGUGAUUGUGGAAAAUCCUUUAGCAGAUAUGUCAGCUUCAGUAAUCAUCAGCGAGAUCACACUGCAAAAGGACCUUAUGAUUGUGGAGAGUGUGGGAAAUCUUAUAGUCGAAAGAGCAGCCUUAUUCAACAUCAGCGAGUCCACACUGGAAAGACAGCUUAUCCCUGUGAGGAGUGCGGGAAAUCUUUUAGUCAGAAGGGCAGCCUUAUUAGCCAUCAGCGUGUUCACACUGGAGAAAGGCCUUAUGAGUGUAGAGAAUAUGGGAAAUCUUUUGGUCAAAAGGGUAACCUCAUUCAACAUCAGCAAGGUCACACUGGAGAGAGAGCUUAUCACUGUGGGGAAUGUGGGAAAUCUUUUCGUCAGAAGUUCUGCUUUAUUAACCAUCAGCGUGUUCACACUGGAGAAAGGCCUUACAAGUGUGGAGAAUGUGGAAAAUCUUUUGGUCAAAAGGGCAACCUCGUUCAACAUCAGCGAGGUCAUACUGGAGAAAGGCCCUAUGAGUGCAAGGAAUGUGGGAAAUCAUUUAGGUACAGAUCCCACCUCACUGAACACCAGAGACUUCACACUGGGGAAAGACCUUACAAUUGUAGGGAAUGUGGGAAAUUAUUUAACAGGAAGUAUCAUCUUCUCGUUCAUGAGAGAGUUCACACUGGAGAAAGGCCAUAUGCGUGUGAGGUAUGUGGGAAAUUAUUUGGUAAUAAGAACUGCGUGACUAUACAUCAGAGGAUUCACACUGGAGAAAGGCCGUAUGAAUGCAAUGAAUGUGGGAAAUCAUUUCUUUCCAGCUCUGCGCUUCAUGUUCAUAAAAGAGUUCAUUCUGGACAAAAGCCUUAUAAGUGCAGUGAAUGUGGAAAAUCCUUUGCUGAAUGUUCCAGUCUCAUUAAACACAGGAGAAUUCACACUGGAGAAAGGCCUUAUGAAUGUACCAAAUGUGGAAAAACAUUUCAGCGAAGCUCUACCCUCCUUCAUCAUCAGAGUUCACACAGGAGAAAGGCCUUAUGAGUGCAGUGAAUAUGGGAAAUCGUUUGCUGAAACAUCCCGUCUCAUUAAACACAGGAGAGUUCAUACUGGAGAAAGGCCUUAUGAGUGCUGUCAAUCUGGGAAACAUCAGAAUGUCUGCUCUCCUUGGUCUUAAGAGACUUCGCAUUGGAACGGAGUCUCAUUCUGUCACCCAGGCUGGAGUGCAGUGGUGCAAUCUUGGCUCACUGCAACUUGGGCCUCCCAGGUUCAAGUGAUUCUCCUACCUCAGCCUCCCAAGGAGCUGAGAUUACGAGUACACCACACCAUGCCCGGCCAAAUACUUGGUUUUCAGUACCACAAGAGCUAUGAGCUGGUUAUCCACUUCAUGUGGAAUCAUAAGUGUCCCCAAGUGACAAUACGUAUAGAUUGCUGGGCAGUGAAACAGUUAAGAUGUCACCGUAGCUUGCUUUCUAUUCAACAUCUUUCUAAGAUUACCUUACUAUUUCUUUUGUUCCAAGUUUGUAUUUCCUCAGAGUUCUCACAUAUGGAAAGGAUACACACUUUGUAGAAACAAGAACUUUAUGUUAUCCAAGUUCUGGGAUAGCCAUGAGCUCCAAUUACCUCAGAGCUCCGAGUCCUCUACUCAGUACCCGUUGAGAUUUAUGUGUUCUGAGGCUUUUGUCUUCUAGCUACUUACUUCAUUCUCCAUGGGUAACGUCAUUCAUCCACAUUAACUAAUUUCCUCACUCCAAGCUCUUUUCUGGAGAUAAUCUCCAGUCCCUGUGCAGACACUGUCAUUGCACUUUCUGCUGAAAUGGUAGUUUCUUGCCAGCAAGGUGAGAUUAUGGAAUCCAGAAUCUUUUUUCAGGGGCCACAUGCCCAUUUCCCCACUUGCAUGAAUGUCGACACUGUAGCCACAGUUUUGGCCGUAAAUGUGAAUUUGGCAAGUAACCACUGUUCCCAAAUUGGGAAAUGUCCCAGUCAGAAGAAGAUUAUCUGGGACACUGAUACUGACAGGGAGAUGGGACAUUCUGAGGGACCCGGAGGCAGGGAGCCACCUCCUCAGCUUCCCUGAGGGCUGCCUAGAAUCUCUCUUGUUUCCUCUCACUCUGAAUUAUUCUUCCUCUCAUGACUGACCAAACACAUGGAACCUCACAAAGUCCAUUUUAAGAGCUUUAUCUUGUGAAGUGAAGAACAUGAAGAUAGUUUGAAUCAAAGUUAUUGAGUGGACACUUAAUGUCUUUAUAACAUUUUUUACAUAUGUGUUUGUGUUUUUUGGGGAGCAUAAUUUGCAAAUGGAAUAUCUGUUAUUUUACUAAGAUGCUUCAUGGAUACAAGAGUUAAAACUUCCUGUCCCAUUUAGUGAAACAAAAGGUUAAGAAAUGUGGAUAAAGCUUGUAAGUUAGAAAUGGCAAGAUAAUCAGCUAUAUGAAGAAUCUCAGCUGGGUGUUUUGGCUCAGGCCUGUAAUCCCAGCACUUUGGGAGGCUGAGGUGGGUGGCUUACAAGGUCAGGAGUUCAAGACCACCCUGGACAAUAUGGUGAAACCCUGUCUCUACUAAAAAUACAAAAAUUACCCAAGCAUAGUGGUGGGUGCCUGUAGUCCCAGCUGCUUGGGAGGCUGAGGCAGGAGAAUUCGUUAAACCUGGGAGGCAUAGGUUGCAGUGAGCCGAGAUUGCACCACUGCACUCCAGCCUGGUGACAGAGCGAGACUCCGUCUCAAAAAAAAAAAAAAAAAAAAAAAAAAAUCUCAAUCCCUAAAUGUUACCUUUUAUAACAGCAGGUUAUAUGGGCUUAGAUAUUAUCCCUAAAUUUUUUUUUUUUUUUUUUUUUGAGACAGAGUCUCACUCUGUCACCCAGGCUGAAGUGCAAUGGCAUGGUCUCGGCUCACUGCAACCUCCGCCUCCCAGGUUCAAGUGAUUCUCUUGCCUCAGCCUCCCAAGUAGCUGGGCCUAUAGGUUCCCUCCACCACGCCCACCUAAUUUUUGUAUUUUUAGUAGAGAUGGGCUUUCACUACGUUAGCCAGGCUGGUCUCAAACUUGUGACCUCAUGAUCCACCCCCCUCAGCCUCCUAAAGUGCUGGGAUUACAGGCAUCUGCCACGGCACUCGGCUUAUCCCUAGAAAUCCUAUGAUAGCAUGAUGUAUAGGCACCUAAAGGCAUGGCACUUGAGAAAUGUGAAUAAGAUUGUAAGUUACAAAUAGCAAGGUACAGUCAGAUGUUAACAGUCUCAGCCCCUAAAUGUCACCUUGUAUUACAGCAUGUUAUAUAAGCACAUACAGGCACAUACAUGAAAUAGUGAUACUUCAUUCUCAGUAAUAUUUUUCAUCCUUCUCACUGGAAAGAUCUUUGAUGAUUUUUAAUCAACAUAGGAGUUUCAAUGAUAUCUAGAAGUUUAAAAGGGCUCGUUCAAACAAAUUAUGACCAUACACCCUGAAGAGUAUGUGUCUGUCUCUUGUGGUGUAAAUUUUUAUUUUAUUACACCCAAUUAUGUUCCCACAAAACCUUUAUAAUUGGGAAAUUAAGGAGCCUUCCUCGGAAAUGGAGGUUGCAAUCAGCUGAGAUGGUACCACUGCACUCUAGCCUGGGCAAAAGAGCAAGGCCCUGCCUCAAAAAAAACAAAACUUUUUUCUUCAUAAACUACAGUUUAUAUAGGCAAAACUUUCAGUACUAAGCAAUUUUAGUCUCUGCAGGCUCUUGUCUUGAAUUAAUACAACUUUUGUUAAUUCUCUUAUGAAGUUAAAUCUUCCUGCUUGUAUGCAACUUAUAUGUUGAAAUUUUUUUGUACAAAAGAUUCAUACAUCUUUCCUGUUUGAAAUUA